ACAACAAAGCUUCCAGAGGGAGAGGAAGGAUGGACGGCACCACUGCCCCUGUCACUAAAUCUGGAGCUGCCAAGUUAGUUAAGAGAAAUUUCCUUGAGGCGCUAAAGUCCAAUGACUUCGGAAAAUUGAAGGCUAUUUUGAUCCAAAGGCAAAUAGAUGUGGACACUGUUUUUGAAGUCGAAGAUGAGAAUAUGGUUUUGGCAUCUUAUAAACAAGGUUACUGGUUGCCUAGCUAUAAAUUGAAGUCUUCCUGGGCCACAGGCCUCCAUCUCUCUGUCUUGUUUGGCCAUGUGGAAUGUCUUCUGGUGCUACUGGACCACAAUGCUACAAUCAACUGUAGACCCAAUGGGAAAACCCCUCUUCACGUGGCUUGUGAAAUGGCCAAUGUGGAUUGUGUUAAGAUCCUCUGUGAUCGUGGGGCAAAGCUCAAUUGCUACUCCUUAAGUGGACACACAGCUUUGCACUUUUGUACAACUCCAAGUUCCAUUCUCUGUGCCAAGCAAUUGGUUUGGAGAGGGGCGAAUGUGAACAUGAAGACCAACAACCAAGAUGAGGAGACGCCCUUGCACACGGCUGCCCACUUCGGCCUUUCGGAGCUGGUGGCCUUCUACGUGGAACACGGGGCCAUAGUGGACAGCGUGAAUGCCCACAUGGAGACCCCCCUGGCCAUCGCCGCCUACUGGGCCCUCCGCUUUAAGGAGCAGGAGUACAGCACGGAGCACCACCUGGUCUGCCGCAUGCUGCUUGACUACAAAGCCGAAGUCAAUGCCCGAGAUGACGACUUUAAAUCUCCCCUCCACAAGGCAGCCUGGAACUGUGACCACGUGCUCAUGCACAUGAUGCUGGAAGCUGGCGCCGAAGCCAAUCUCAUGGAUAUCAACGGCUGUGCUGCCAUCCAGUACGUGCUGAAGGUCACCUCCGUGCGCCCUGCUGCCCAGCCUGAGAUCUGCUACCAGCUCCUGUUGAACCAUGGGGCUGCCCGAAUAUACCCUCCACAGUUCCAUAAGGUGAUACAGGCCUGCCAUUCUUGUCCUAAAGCAAUUGAAGUUGUAGUCAAUGCCUAUGAACACAUCAGAUGGAACACAAAGUGGAGAAGAGCUAUCCCCGAUGAUGACUUGGAGGGCAUCAGAAAAUGACAGAACAGAGCAAAAUUUGGAGGUCUAGGACUGCUUAUACUUCUCAACAUGGCAGUGUUCAAGUGCUAAAUUAUUCACUGAAGCACUGACGUCAUUACAGUCUUUCAGGGAUCCCAGGACUCCAAAUACUGCUGAAGUCAGAUGGACAACAAAAGGUCUCUUAGGAUGAUCCAUCAAGGAAAACACAGGCAUCAGCAAAUUGUUCCUAAGCAACAUCUGGUUAAUUCUAUGACAAAAAUACAAAGAAGCUGAAAACUGUUUACUCCAACUAGCACUGCAGUGUGGCACAAAGAAAAAUAUAUGGACUUUGGAAUUCAAUGGCUUGAGUUUUAAUCUUGAUUGUUCCAUUUAAUAUCUUUGUGAACUUGGGUCAGUUUCUUAAUUCAAGUGUCAAUUUCUUUAUUUAGGUAAUGGUGAUUAACUACUUGACAUUCCAGACUCUUUGGGGGAAUUUAUUUAUUUUUAUUUAUUUUAUUUUAUUUUUUUGAGAUGGGGUCUCACUCUGUUGCUUAGGCUGGAGUGCAGUGGCACAAUCUCGGCUCACUGCAACCUCCGCUUCCCAGGUUCAAGGGAUUCUGUCAUGUCAGCCUCCCAAGUAGCUGGGAUUACAGGUGCAUGCCAUCACGCCCAGCUAAUUUUUCUAUUUUUUGAUAGACAGGGGGUUUCACUAUGCUGACCAGGCUGGUCUCAAACUCCUGUGAUCCACCUGUCUCGGCCUUCCAAAGUGCUGGGAUUACAGGCAUGAGCCACUGUGCCCAGCCAGAUAUGACAGGGUUUCUAAGACAUUUAUGUGCACAGGCCAAAGAUCCAGCUUUUUUUUUUUUCUUUUUAUUGCAUUUUAACUGCAACGAUUUUCCCGUGGUACAGACUCACUCUCUGAAACAAACUGUCCCAAGCUGUUUUGUUAAGGGUUCAUUGCUCCUGGCAGUUUGGCCUAAAGGAGGCACUGUAGGAGAAUUUUCUCCCUGCUGUGAAUCACAGCUAUGGAAUUACACACAGCUUUCAUUUCUAAAGGCCGUCUUGAAGAAAAUUAAACCAGAAAGAUCAAGAAAGGUAAAUAGGUAUUCUAUGGCACCUUUCUUUAAUCUCCUGGUUACAGUUUCAAAGAAUUUUGCUCUUGCCUUCAUUGGAAAGAGAUCUGGGUAUCAGGAAAUGAUUUUAGAACCAUAGGUUUCUGUCCUGUGGUUACAUAAUCUGGAAGGAAAAAAACAACAUUGCAGUUAGUUUCUCUCUGUGUAGCACUGAAAUAGACAAUUUCAUUAGUAAUUCCAUUCAUUCAAUUUCCCUUCUUUCUUUCUUCCUCCCUGUUUUUCUUUCUGUCUCUUUCAUAUUCUCUCCAUUUCUCUCUUCCCUUAUUGUUUCUUGUUCUCAUUCCUGGGUGUGGUUUUGUUUUUGUUUUUGUUUUGCUUCUUCGUGGCUAGGAUCUCAGUGUGAGCAUGUACUUAUGUAGAGUAAAUGUUGAUAUAUUCUUAGGGUCUGUCAACAACUGGCAAGAAUAGCAUUUGUUGUCUUUCUAGCAAUAGAUUGCAGGUGAGAGAUCAGGACCAAGCUAGGAUUAAAAACUACCAAAGAGACAGGAGAAAAGCCUCCAAAAUGAGAUAUGCAUGUUUCUGCCCAUCCCAGGCAAUGCCAGAGAAGCCUAAUCAUGCCAUCUGAGUCACAGGUGUCCCAUGCACUUUUGCACAUAGUCAGACAUCUCCACCGGUAUGGUCACAGAGUUGCUCCCUUCUGGAAAAUCAUAAAAGAAUUAGUUAUUGAGAUAAUAUAGCUGAAUAGGUAGCCAUACAGAGUAAUGCAUAGAAUCAGACAUGCCAGAGUUGGAACUCCUCCCUGUCACUUAAUAUUUUCUGAGGCCCAGUUCCCACCUUUGUAACUAGGAGCAAUAAUUGUUUAGUACAAUGUCAGGCACCUGGUUAACUUUUAAUAAAUUGCAAUUAUUAUUAUAGUCCCACCCUGCUUGAAUUCUAGAUUUCUGUAAGUGACUGACUUGUAGACCCUGCACAUUCCACAAAUGGUUAGACACACACAUAUCUAACAAAAAUAUGUGAGCAUAUGAAUAGAUAUUCAGUGAUAUUCCAGUUGCAGCCCACUGAAGGAAAUCUGCCCAUUUGUAGACAUGGGCCGCAUCUAAAUAAAUUAAUAUGGGCCCUCUUUCAAUGUGUAGAUAUUUGAUUUAGUUUCCAAUGAUUCUUAAAUAUUUUUUUUUCUGCGUUGGAGCAAGGUUGACUCAUUGAACAUAUGCUGUGUCUGUAUCUUAUUUUGAUAUUAUGUGGUGCUUGAAUUUGAGCUCUUCAGGGAUGGCAAAAGUGGGGUGUGUUAUUUUUUACACCUACGGCAGACAAUAAUAACCAACCAAAAUAUUCUCUCCUUUUGAGCCCAGACUCAGCCGCAGAGUUCUUCUCAGUACAGUGUAAGGACUGUUACUUCCAAUUGCUUAGAGUUGAUAGGCAAGGUGAAAUACAUUUGUCAUCCUUGGAUUUCAUUCUCAAUCCUCUCACAGGCUCUUGGUCUCGAAUUGUAUAAAUAAAAAGCUGGAUGGAGUUAGAAGGCAGGGCUGCCGGCACAGGAUUUCACUUUUGGUUUUCUUUGGUCAGGAGAAGCAUAGAAUUUUGCCAUUUAUUCAACAAAUAUUUAUUGAGCUGGACUCUGUACCUGCUGUGGAUUCAAAGGUGAAUAAUGGCAAAGUCUUGGCCUUCAUUGGGAAACUGAUGAGUCUGCACAUUCAGAUACCUGGGGUGCUUUCAAAAAUACCACUCCAAUUUCCCACGUCCCCUUUUAAAAGCUUUAAUAGGCGAAUUAGGUUAAGUACCUCACUUAUACUAUGUUGUAAAUGCCUGUCUGCCAGUCUCUACCACCAGGCUGUAACCUCCUUAAAAGAAGGAACUGUAAUCUCUUCAGUUUUUUAAAAGAUUAAGGUAAAAUUUACCAAUAGUGAAAUACACAACUUUAAAAUGGAUAAUUGUAUGAAUGAUUACAAGUGUAUAUACCCUUAUAAUCAACACUUUAGUCAAGGUAAACAAUACAUUUAUUACCCCAGAAUAUCUUCAUGUAUUCUUUUGUCUCUUUCUAGUAAAUUCCUAUCUCCCACAGGCAACCACUGUACUGUUUCUAUCACCAUGGGUUAGGUUUACUUGGUUUUGAACUUCACAAAAACAGAAUUAUACAGCAUAUAUUCUUAUGUGUUUGGCUUCAUUCUCGUAACAUAAUAUUUUGGAGAUUCAUCCAUAUUUUGCAUAUAUUAGUAGUUUAUACUUCUUUAUUGCUUAAUCGUGUUCCAUCCUGUGAAUAUACCAAAAUAAAUAUUUAUGCAUUCUCCUAGCGAUGAAGAUUUGGGUUAUUUCCAGCUUAGGGUAAUAAUAGAUGUGAGGGUUAGUUUUGUGUGUUAACUUGGCUAGGCUAUGUGUAUCCAGAUAUUUGGUUAAACAUCAGUUUAGAUGUUGCUGUGGAAAUAUUUUUUAGAAGUAAUAAACAUUUAAGUUAAUAGGUUUUGAGUAAAGCAGAUCACUCUCCAUAAUAUGGGGUUUGUUCUCAUCCCAUCGGUUGAAUGCCUUACAAGAAAAAGACUGAGGUCCCCUGAGAAAGUGGGAAUUCUGCCUCCAGAUUGUCUUCAGAUUCAUGACUGAAACAUUAACUCUUCCCUGGGUCUCCAGCCUGCUGGCUUCCCCUGCAGAUUUCAAACUUGUUAGUCCCUAUAAUCAUCUGAGCCAAUCUCUUAACAUAUUUUUUAUCUCUCUUUCUAUGUAUAUAUAACCUACGGGUUCUGUUUCUUUGGAGAGUCUUGACUAAUACAAUGGAUGAAUAUGCUGUAAACACUCUUGUUCAAAUCUUUUUUGUGGGCAUGUUUCCAUUUCCCUUGGGCAAAUAUCUAGAAGUGAAAUUCAAGGUCAGCCACUUUAAUUUUACAAGAAAGUACCAAACUGUUUUCCAAAGUGAUGUACAUGUUUGCAUUUCUACCAGCAAUAUGAGAGUUCCGGUUGCUGUCAUUCUUGUCAAUAGUUGGUGAUGUAAGUCUUUUUAAUUUUAGCCAUUCUGAUAGGUAAAUAGUGAUAAGUCUCUGUACUUUUCAUUUGUAUUUCUCUGAGGGCUAAUGAUGUUAAACAGCUUUUCACUUGCUUAUUUGCUAUUUGUGUAUCUUCUUUGGUGAACUGUCUGUUGGAAUAGUUUGUCAUUUGUUCCCUUUGUAUCUCAACUCCUAGCAUUUAAUAGUCACUCAGUGUAUACUGUUUUAAGAAUGAAUGAAUGUUAUAUUGUCCAUCAGUGAUUAUUCCAAAAUGAUUACUAAACUUUUGUGUUAUUAUUUGUAAUGCUUAUAAAGUACUCAGCAAUGGUACCUAACACAUAGUCAACACCCCACAGUUGGUAGCUAUUAGUGCCAUCCCUAUUUUGACUAUGAGGAAAUGAGGACUAGAAAAGUUAUGUUAAUCAAGGUCUAGUUACUAAUUAUCAAAAUUGCUGCUGAAAUCUGGACUUCUCAAAUCUGUAUUUCAUGUUUUGAGUUUUUUGUUACCAGUAGCUUGACUAAGUAUUAGAUUAAGCAUUAACUGUGUUGCUUCAUUCAUUUUUUAACUCUUAUUUAUAGCAAACCUGACAUGGAAAAUAUAAUGAUGCUAAUUCCUUUACAUGCUUUAAUUUAUUUAAUUCUUACUAUAACCCUAUGAGGAAAAUACUAUUAUUUUUAUUUUAUGGACGAUUAAACUGUAGUAUAGACAGAUUAUGCAAUUGCCUAGGAUCUCACAGGUAAUUAAAGGUAGAGGCAGGAUUCAAACUCAAUCACUUGCAUACCAAUGCCUGUGUGUUUUGCUUUGUUUUAAAACCAUUAUGCUAUCCUGUUUCUUAUGACAAAAUUAAUUUUGGACAUGUUGAUUUUGAGGGGCUUAUGGGAUAGCAGGAUGGGGAUGUCCAGUAAAUCCCUGACACUUAGGAGAGAGUUACGGGAGGAUGGGGAUAUAGAAAGAGAGUGCACUUGAUAACUACAGUGCUAGACCAUAUUAAGAAAGUGGUUAAAGUGCCUGAAAUAUUGGAAGAUGGAGGAAUUUCACUAGAUUCCAUUCCAGAAAGUUCCAUAGGAGACUCCAUUUUUUUUUUUUUGAGAUGGAGUCUCGCCCUGUCGCCCAGGCUGCAGUGCAGUGGUGCGAUCUCCACUCACUGCAAGCUCCGCCUCCCGGGUUCACCCCAUUCUCCUGCCUCAGCCUCCCUAGUAGCUGGGACUACAGGUGCCCGCCAUCACGCCCGGCUAAUUUUUUUGUAUUUUUAGUAGAGACAGGGUUUCACCGUGUUCGCCAGGAUGGUCUCGAUCUCCUGACUUCGUGAUCCGCCCGCCUUGGGCUCCCAAAGUGCUGGGAUUAUAGGCGUGAGCCACCGCGCCCGGCCGAGACUCCAUUUUUAAAAUGGAUUUACGUUGUUCACAAGAACAGGUCUGUAAUGAUGAAAUCUUACAGUCUGUUUUUAAGAUACUCUAAAAUAUUUUGGUUGCUGUUUGUUAUUAGACUCUGACAGGUGGACCUAGGUUGCCUGCCCAGAGGGUCUAGGAGCUCACAAUUUCUCUAAAGACCCCUUUUCUGUUUACUGGAAACCCUAGGAGCUUCCUUAGGGGCUUGUCAGGCCAAGCUGACUAAUCCUUCCUUCUGCUCAAAUUUCACUCUUCUGAAAAGGGAGUUUGACGAGCAGGGAGUGAGUCACUAGCUCCAAGAUGGCAGCAAGGAGCACUGGUGUUAAUCUGUGUUAUCUUAGUUCCCACAGGGUGAGUAAUCAUGCCUGGCCAAAUCUCACUGGGCAAAACAGGUGCAAGUUUCCAAAGGAAGGCUUUGUGACCAUAAUAGGAGGUUAGCUGAAAUCCAACCUGUAUUUACUCCUUGCAACAGAAUACUUUAUGAACCAUGGUUUACAGGAACAUCCAGGUUCCCUAAAAAUUUAUCUCUUCCAUGAUGAUGGAAACACAGCAACGUACACAGACUGGACCUGGGGACUAUCUUAGCUUCUGAAGACUUGCACAGCAGGUCUAAAAGUCCAAGGCUGCCUCCUGACACUCCAGAGAGGAACUAUGUGACACAGAGAGACUAAGCCAGGCCCUGCCCACAGGGUUGCACACACAAACAUGUUUUCCAAGCCCUUUAUACACUCAGCAGGGAACACGCCGUUCUCUCUGGGAGGUUGCCAGAAACUUAUAAGAGAGUCUGAUCAGUGCCAAGAAUAGACAAGCAAGGCUUCUCUCCUGUCUCGGAAGGGGACACUGUGUGGUGCUGAGUUAUUACCGCCCCUCUGUGCUCCUCUAGCCUUCAAAAGCAAACCUGAAACUGUUUCCCUGCACUUCUUAAUCUCUUGAUCAGUCGAAAAAUUAUUGCUGGAGCUCGCUAUACCUCUUUGGGCACCUGUAAUCUUGUUGUCCAAACCCAAAUGCAAAUAUGUUCCCUCUGCUUGCAUUUGUUUUGCAUCUCAGAGACUCAGGCCGUGGAUCUUUGAGGUAGAACCCAAGGAAAAUAGUCAACAACUUUGUCCAUUUGCCCAGGAAGAGUCUGAGUUGUUGCUGUUCCUCAUUAGUCCUCUGCUUUAGCUUCAGCAAGGACGGCAAAGGUUACUUGAAAUUCAGCCAGUGCAGGCAAUGUUGAGAAAAAACUUGACUCUUCUCUUCCAUGUACAGGAUGUCUUUCCAACCCCUUCCCCAAAGUUUUCUUAAAUCCUUGGUGUCUUCAACUUGGCCCCAGCUCUAAAAUUAAAUAUUUACCAUGUUUUUUCCUCUAUAAUAAUACUGGGAAGAAUCAACCAUGCGUUUUUAAAUAAAAGUCUCGCUUUUGUCACGCAGGCUGGAGUGCAAUGGUGUGAUCUUGGCUCACUGCAACCUCCAACUACCAGGUUCAAGCAAUUCUCCUGCCUCAGCCUCCCGAAUAGCUGGGACUACAAGCGCAUGCCACCAUGCCAGGCUCAUUUUUGAAUUUUUAGUAGACACACGGUUUUGCCUUAUUGGCCAGGCUGGUCUCAAACUCCUCACCUCGGGACAUCCACUCGGCUUGGCCUCCCUAAAUGCUGGGAUUACAAGCAUGAGCCACUGCGCCUGACCAGUUUUUAAAUAAAGCACUUUAAAUGAGUUAUUCACA